AGUUUACUUCCUGCGUCCCCGGACGCCGUAGGUGGAAAGGCGAACCCUGAGUGGAGGAUGUUCCCGCUGCCUAAAGAAUGAUUGACUGUAAGAUUGAUUUGCCAACAGUGGGGUGCUUUUCUCUCGAUACACACAGCAAUAGACAGAACGGAAAUUCUGGGAUCCUAAUCUAGCAUGGAAGAGAAAGGCCGGGAGCACGAAGGCAGCAGGACCUCUUCCUUCUCUUUUUUCUUUUUCUAUACUUCUUUUCUCCCCUCUACUUAUUUAUCUCUUUCAAGAAAUGAGACUGGGCACAGUGGCUCACGCCUGUAAACCCAGCUCUUUGGGAAGCCGAGGCGGGAGGAUCGCUUGAGGCCAGGAGUUCGAGACCAGCCUGGGCAACAUAGUGAGACCACCUCCCCCAACCUCUACAAAAGAAAAAAAAAAUGAAUGAAAUGACUUAAGUUCUUACCUCCAUUCUUCUUUUUGGAUCCGAGGUAACUGCACUUUUGUGAGAUUAUAAAUAUACCACGGAGGGUAACGAAGCUACAGAAGAAUGGAAGAAGACAGCCUGGAAGACUCAAACCUUCCUCCAAAAGUUUGGCAUUCUGAGAUGACGGUGUCAGUGACAGGCGAACCACCUAGUACCGUAGAAGAAGAAGGAAUACCUAAAGAAACAGACAUAGAAAUCAUCCCAGAAAUCCCGGAAACUCUAGAGCCACUGUCCCUUCCAGAUGUGCUGAGGAUCUCGGCAGUUCUGGAGGACACCACAGACCAGCUCUCUAUUCUGAACUACAUCAUGCCCGUUCAGUACGAAGGGAGACAGAGCAUCUGCGUGAAAAGCAGAGAAAUGAAUCUAGAAGGAACGAAUCUAGACAAACUUCCAAUGGCCUCAACAAUCACAAAAAUACCCAGUCCGUUAAUAACUGAGGAAGGACCCAACUUGCCAGAAAUCAGACACAGAGGCCGGUUCGCUGUGGAGUUUAACAAAAUGCAGGAUCUUGUCUUCAAAAAACCUACAAGGCAGACCAUCAUGACUACGGAGACACUGAAGAAAAUUCAGAUUGAUAGGCAGUUUUUCAGCGAUGUGAUUGCAGAUACCAUUAAGGAGUUGCAAGAUUCGGCCACUUACAACAGUCUCCUGCAAGCUUUGAGCAAAGAGAGGGAAAACAAAAUGCAUUUCUAUGACAUCAUUGCCAGGGAGGAAAAAGGAAGAAAACAGAUAAUAUCACUUCAAAAACAGCUAAUUAAUGUCAAAAAGGAAUGGCAAUUUGAAGUCCAGAGUCAGAAUGAGUAUAUUGCUAACCUCAAGGACCAACUGCAAGAGAUGAAGGCAAAAUCCAACUUGGAGAAUCGCUACAUGAAAACCAAUACCGAGCUGCAGAUUGCCCAGACCCAGAAAAAGUGUAACAGAACAGAGGAACUCUUGGUGGAAGAGAUUGAGAAACUCAGGAUGAAAACCGAAGAAGAGGCCCGGACUCAUACAGAGAUUGAAAUGUUCCUUAGAAAGGAGCAGCAGAAACUUGAGGAGAGGCUGGAGUUCUGGAUGGAGAAAUACGAUAAGGACACAGAAAUGAAACAGAAUGAACUAAAUGCUCUCAAAGCCACAAAGGCCAGUGACUUAGCACACCUUCAAGACCUGGCAAAGAUGAUAAGAGAGUAUGAACAGGUCAUCAUUGAAGAUCGUAUAGAAAAGGAGAGGAGCAAGAAGAAGGUAAAACAGGAUCUCUUGGAAUUAAAGAGCGUUAUAAAGCUCCAGGCCUGGUGGCGAGGCACUAUGAUACGGAGAGAAAUUGGUGGUUUCAAGAUGCCUAAAGACAAAGUUGAUAGCAAGGAUUCAAAAGGCAAAGGUAAAGGCAAGGAUAAGAGGAGAGGCAAGAAGAAGUGACCAAGUUCUCUUUUGUGUUUUCUGCUGGUAUUCUGGAGGUGGGAAGGACUUGGAGAGAGUUAAGAAACACCUGGUACCUCAAAGAUGACUCAUCUACAGGUUGUUUCCUAUUGAGACUUUCCCAGGGAAGCCUGAUUUCACUUUGCCUGUUAAUUUCACUCUGCCUGUUAGGUGGGUUUUCAAACCCUGAUUUAGGAUUACACCAUUGACUUAGGGCUUCCUCAUACCUUGCUGGGAAGAAGUUUCUAGUAGUCCUGUGAAGAUUCAUUCUUCUUGCUCUUUCUCAGCAGAACAAAGGAGUUCACUGGCUUAGCUACAGUGACGCAUUGAAACUUGAGUAAUUCCUGUAAUGUCAGAUUUUGAUUUUACCCAAUUUGUCUGUAGUGAAAAAACUCUUAUGAGCAAAAGUAUUCAGUAGGAAUUACAAUAUGAUGUUAUUAGCUGUCCAGCAUAAUAUAUACACAGCAAAGUUUUAAUAAAUGUUGGUUCCUGCCUGCCUUUUA